GAACGAGUCAACCGGAUCGGUGACUGUGGAGGGCGAGCUGAGCCCUGGCCGCCGCCACAAUGGGCCGCGAGUUUGGGAAUCUGACGCGGAUGCGGCAUGUGAUCAGCUACAGCUUGUCACCGUUCGAGCAGCGCGCCUAUCCGCACGUCUUCACUAAAGGAAUCCCCAAUGUUCUGCGCCGCAUUCGGGAGUCUUUCUUUCGCGUGGUGCCGCAGUUUGUAGUGUUUUAUCUUAUCUACACAUGGGGGACUGAAGAGUUCGAGAGAUCCAAGAGGAAGAAUCCAGCUGCCUAUGAAAAUGACAAAUGAGCAACGCAUCCGGAUGACGGUUCCCUGUCUCUGAAAGACCUUUCUCUGGAAGAGGAGUCUGCAUUGUAGUGUCUCAAAGACACAAUAAACUUCCUAUGGUCUGCACUGUUGUGAUAUUACAUUUUUGUGAGUAGAAUCCUGUGUGACCACUAAUAUUCAAGUUCAUGAAGCGCCCCUCCUCAGCAUGAGUCUUGAAGUUUUGCCUGGUCUCGGGUUUUGGUGAAAGAGCAGGGCUCCCCCUUUGUUCCAUUAUCUACAAGAAAGUAGCUGCAGGUACUCCUGCAUCUAACCAUUUGUGGGUGACAUGGGCUAUGGCGAGUGCUGGUUCUUGGCCCUCUGCUCCCAUAGCAACAAUAAAGUCUACUAACUAUAUUGUAAUUAGUAUGUGUCAGGGACGCUUUUAUUUUUUAUUUUUUGAGAUGGAGUCUUGCUCUCUCACCCAGGCUGGAGUGCAGUGGUGUGAUCUCGGCUCACUGCCAUCUGUGCCUCCUGGGUUCAAACGAUUCUCCUGUCUCAGCCUCCGAGUAGCUGGGAUUACAGGUGCAGGACACCACACCUGGCUAAUUUUUUGUAUUUUUAGUAGAGACAGGUUUCACCAUGUUGGCCAGGCUGGUCUGGAACUCCUGACCUCAGAUGAUCUGUGCGCCUCAGCCUCCCAAAGUGCUGGGAUUACAGGCGUAAGCCAUGGUGCUCUGGGCCUCAAAUACUCUUCUUAGCUACACAAAUGAACUGUUAAACCUCACAAGCACCUUUAACGUAUCCUCAUUUGGCAGAUGAGGAAAUGGGCACAGAGAGAUUAAGUAAUUUGCCAGAAAUUAUACAGCAGUGAAUGGUGGAGUCUUGCACUAAAGUGAUGCUCUUAAAACUAUGCUCUAUUGCAGGGGUGUCCAAUCUUUUAGCUUCCCUGGGCCACACAUAAAAUACGCUAACAUUACAAUAGCUGAUAAGCUUUAAAAAAUGGCAAAAAAAACCCUCAGCGUUUUAGAAAGUUUACAAAUUUUUGUUGGGUCGGAUUCAAAGCCAUCCUGGGCUGCUUGCUGCCCAGGACUGCGGUUGGACAAGCUUGCUCUACUGCCUUUCCUCCUAAGGCAGGCCUUAGCCUGAGGGGAUAUCAGCUAUAAAACGGAUGAGGUGAUCUCUUAGCCUCCACAGCAGUUUUCUGUUUCUGUGCCAGGAGGCCAACAAUGUUUUCAACCAUAUGUGGUUCAUAAAGCCUCAAAGAUUUACUCUGGCCCUUUAUGAAUAAAGUUUACCCCUGAUCUAAA